AGUUGGCUCGGCGGCAGCGGAGCGGCCGGAGCUGCGGUGCGGACCGGGGCCGCGCGGCGUGGCGCGGGGAGCGGCGGCGGCGGCAGAGCCAGAGCAACAUGGCGCCGGUGGGCGGGGGCGGGCGCCCGGUCGGCGGACCGGCCCGCGGGCGCCUCCUCCUGGCGGCGCCGGUGCUGCUGGUGCUGCUGUGGGCGCUGGGGGCCCGGGGCCAGGGCAGCCCCCAGCAGGGCACGAUCGUGGGCAUGAGGCUGGCGAGCUGCAACAAGUCGUGUGGGACGAACCCGGAUGGCAUCAUCUUCGUGUCCGAGGGCAGCACCGUGAACCUGAGGCUGUACGGCUACAGCCUGGGCAACAUCUCCAGCAACCUGAUCUCCUUCACCGAGGUGGACGAUGCCGAGACCCUCCACAAGUCCACCAGCUGCCUCGAGCUCACCAAGGACCUGGUCGUCCAGCAGCUGGUCAACGUGAGCCGCGGGAACACGUCCGGCGUGCUGGUGGUGCUCACCAAGUUCCUCCGGAGGAGCGAGAGCAUGAAGCUGUAUGCACUGUGCACCCGGGCCCAGCCCGACGGGCCCUGGCUGAAGUGGACGGACAAGGACUCACUGCUCUUCAUGGUGGAGGAGCCUGGGAGGUUCCUGCCUCUCUGGCUGCACAUUCUCCUAAUUACGGUGCUGCUGGUGCUGUCGGGCAUAUUUUCUGGCCUCAACCUCGGGCUUAUGGCCCUGGACCCCAUGGAGCUGCGCAUCGUGCAGAACUGUGGCACCGAGAAGGAGAGGCGCUAUGCCCGCAAGAUUGAGCCCAUCCGGCGCAAGGGCAACUACCUUCUCUGCUCGUUGCUCCUAGGGAACGUGCUGGUCAACACCUCCCUCACAAUCCUUCUAGACAACCUCAUCGGGUCCGGCCUCAUGGCGGUGGCCUCCUCCACCAUUGGCAUUGUCAUCUUUGGGGAGAUCCUACCUCAGGCCCUGUGCUCCCGACAUGGGCUGGCUGUGGGUGCCAACACCAUCCUUCUCACCAAAUUCUUUAUGCUACUCACCUUCCCCCUCAGUUUUCCCAUUAGCAAGCUCCUGGACUUUUUUCUGGGCCAGGAGAUUCGCACUGUUUACAACCGGGAGAAGCUGAUGGAGAUGUUGAAGGUGACGGAGCCCUAUAAUGACCUCGUGAAAGAGGAGCUCAAUAUGAUCCAGGGUGCCCUGGAACUACGGACCAAAACUGUAGAGGAUAUCAUGACCCAGCUCCAGGACUGCUUCAUGAUCCGCAGCGAUGCCAUCCUGGACUUCAACACCAUGUCGGAGAUAAUGGAAAGCGGCUAUACUCGCAUCCCGGUGUUCGAAGACGAGCAGUCCAAUAUUGUAGAUAUUCUCUACGUCAAAGACUUGGCCUUUGUGGACCCCGAUGACUGCACCCCCCUCAAGACUAUCACUCGCUUCUAUAACCACCCGGUGCACUUUGUCUUCCAUGACACCAAGUUGGAUGCCAUGCUGGAGGAGUUCAAGAAGGGGAAGUCCCACCUGGCCAUCGUGCAGAAGGUAAACAACGAGGGUGAGGGUGACCCCUUCUACGAGGUCCUGGGCCUGGUCACCCUGGAGGACGUGAUCGAGGAGAUCAUCAAGUCGGAGAUCCUGGACGAGUCCGACAUGUACACUGACAACCGAAGCCGGAAGCGGGUGUCUGAGAAGAACAAGCGUGACUUCUCUGCCUUCAAGGAUGCGGACAAUGAGCUCAAAGUGAAAAUCUCCCCGCAGCUCCUCCUGGCCGCUCAUCGCUUCCUAGCCACAGAGGUCUCUCAGUUUAGCCCCUCCCUGAUAUCAGAGAAGAUCCUGCUGCGGCUACUCAAGUACCCAGAUGUCAUUCAGGAACUCAAGUUUGACGAGCACAAUAAGUACUACGCCCGCCAUUACCUGUACACCCGAAAUAAGCCGGCCGACUACUUCAUCCUCAUCCUGCAGGGGAAGGUGGAGGUGGAGGCAGGGAAGGAGAACAUGAAGUUUGAGACGGGCGCCUUCUCCUACUAUGGGACUAUGGCCCUGACCUCGGUCCCCUCCGUGCCUUCAGUCCAGGUCGGGUGUCCGCCUGGCAAGCGGAACUCCCUGCUCUGCUGGCUCACAGACCGUUCCCCAGCACACCCCACCCCACUCAGCCGCUCAGCCUCCCUCAGUUACCCAGACCGCACAGACGUCUCAACUGCAGCAACCUUGGCAGGCAGCAGCAACCAGUUUGGCAGCUCUGUCCUGGGCCAGUACAUCUCUGACUUCAGCGUCCGGGCACUCGUGGACUUGCAGUACAUCAAGCCUCAAUCCUGGCCCUGUUUCUCCAGGCCUGGUGAUAGGGUCUGCCUCCCAGCCCCUCCCUCCAUGAACUCAUCCCUUCCUCAUGCAGAUCACUCGGCAGCAGUACCAGAACGGGCUGCUGGCUUCUCGCAUGGAGAACAGCCCUCAGUUUCCCAUAGACGGGUGCACCACCCACAUGGAGAACUUGGCCGAGAAGUCUGAGCUGCCUGUGGUGGACGAGACCACAACUCUUCUCAACGAGCGUAACUCCUUGCUGCACAAAGCCUCCCACGAGAAUGCCAUCUGACAGGAGGGCCCGGGGCCCCCUGCCCACCCUGCGGGGGCCUCCCCAGUGGGCCCACAUGAAGAGAGGGAACCUGUUAGUCCAGAAAGGAUACGGAUAGAUAGCCUGUCUGACUGAACAGCCAGAUGGCCCCCAGCCUAUGGGGGAUCUGGCCUCUGCCAGGGACCUCUGAGUAGCUCUGAGGUGGCACUGUCCAGCCCUGGAUAGGGGGGGCAGUGGGCCAGCUACCGUAAGCAAAGGCUGUUUUUUACUGAGAGAAUUUCUAAAGUAGGCUCAUCACUUUUUUUUAAAUAUCAUUUUGGGAAGGGAAGACAGGGUUAAGGAACUUUAUUUAAAAAAAAAAUAUUUUUUUCCUAAAAACUAUAAAAGAGGAAGGGUUUCUUGUCCCGGGAAGCAACGGACAUAAUCUGUUCCCAGCCAUGGCCUUCCAGCUUGUGUCCCUGAUUCAGGGAGCUCUCCCUUCCUCCUCCUCCUCCUCCUCCGGAGGUGGGAUCCCAGAGCCUGCCAGUGGAGGCUUAUCUGUUGGGAGGAAGACAGCUCUUCACAGAAGCAAAGAACAAAAUGGCAUGGAGAUCAGCUGCCUGAGCACCUGCGCUGUAGCUUAUCUGACAACGCUGAGGCCACGAGCUCCUGGGUAGCUGUGAUCAGGGACAUGAUAAUCUGAGCUAUGCAGAGGAGCACAUCUGUUGUCAACUGCUGUACCCAGAAAUCUAGAACUCUGCCGACAGCCUCUCCUGGUGAGUCGGGACUCAGCUGAGGACACAUCCCCACCCUGCCUCCCAUCUGGCCCUUUGGACAACUGGCCCUUUGUGACAGGGCUGACUCAAGUGUUAGGCAGGGUCUCAGGCCUUUGAUUGCUCACCCCUGCUCCCCAGGCCCUGCCCUCACUUUUACCAAAGGUUCUCCCUCGGCGGGAGGGCAUCUGUGUUGGAGGUGAUUUGUCUGGGUUCUUCCUUUUGGUUCCAGAAGGAACUGUCAGUCAUCAGCAUCUGCGUUGUUAGCAGUCAGUACCACCCCCGCCCCACAAUGACAGUCAAGGCUGACUUGUUGACUGAAGCCUUUUUCCCAGACCCCUUAUUUCGAAUCCCCAAGCUUCAGUCCCUCUUGGGGGUGGAGACAAGAGGACAUGUGGGAAGCCACGGAAGCAGGUUCUUUAUGUCCUCUCCUCUGUGGCUGGCAAGGCUCACCUGGCCUUAUCCACCCACUUAUGGAACCUCAGGAGAGGAGGGCUCCUCCUAAAGGCAUGCAGCUUGCAGCCCCUCUUUCUCACACGUGUGAUCCUAGCGUGAGAGGUCAUCCUGCCCUUGCUGAAGUUAGUAGUACUGUACUAAGAGCUCUGCCCUCAUGUGAAUUCCUGCCCUGGCGCCUCUUCCCUGGGGCUGAAUCAGGCCCUGCUGCAAAACUCCAGGCUUCCCAGGGUUGGGGAGGCUGUGGGACCAAGGUCCAUGUUGGUCCUUCCACUGGGUGCAGCAGGAGCUGGGUCCCGAGAGCCUGGCAGGUGAAACUCUGCAGGCCUUCCGCCUGAUUAUUAUUUAUUCACUCCUUUCCUCACCCCAAGUGCCCUGCUCUCCAGGUGCCUAGAGUAUCCUAACUCUUAGGACCAGGGAUUGUCUUGCACCAAGUAUGCCUACCCCUGGCCAGUCUGAGGUCUCCUAGCCAUAGAACUGACUCCUGGAAGCCUGGAGAGAAGGUGGUGACACCCAUGGGUUCUCAACUGUAAGGAAAAAAGACACCAGACUUUUGUUCCCUAGUGGGGGAAAGCCCUUAGUCUUGUACAGGAGCAGCUUGCUCCCAAGUCCUUUUGGAAGCUGGCAGAGCUAUAUUCCUGACAGCCCUGACUGCCAGGUAGAGCAAAAGACAUUGGUGGGGGUAUGUGAAGCAAAAGGGGCAGGUGCACACACCUCCACAGUGACCUCUGUGCACACGGUUACCACCAACUGGCUGGCCCUCCUCCUCUUCCCUGGCCCAUUGAUCAUCCCUUCUCACAGAGGGUCAUCAUUAUUUCCAAAUAUUGUUUGUCUGAUGACUUCCUCUUCCCAGUGCAAUUUUUCCCUUCCUAUUUCAACCUCUGGUUCCUGGGAUGAGCCAUACCCUGGAACUGGCCCACCCACUGUGUCUUCCACGUAAGGGAGACCUUUGCAAAGGGCAUCCAAAUGGGUAGGCAGGUGACAGCCGCCGUAUUUAUUUUGCAUAAUAUUUUAAUUUGUAUAUUUUUGUGAUUUAUUUUGGCGUUAUGAGUUUGACUCUCGGGGAGUUUUGUUGUUAUGACUCUUGUGUCUUUUGUCACAAAACAAUGAUAUUUGCUAAACGAUAUAUGGAAUUUAUUUUUGAUUGGUAAUAAAAAAUCAAAUAUGUAUAAA